AGUCAACAGUAGAGAAUCCAAGAUAGAUCAACUCUCCCUAAAGGCUGACAGUGAACUCUUGGGGCCGUUUUAUUCUCUGAGGUUAGCAAGGAGUCAUCUACUAGCCAUUCAGGAGGCCAGCUGGGAAGACAAAAUAGGCACCCCAAACUCAGCAACUUCAUAACACCUUCCUCUCCCCGCCUGAAGCCUUAAACUGCAUCAAGUCAAAGAAACCUGGGGCAAAUCCUUAACAUGUUUUUGACUGCAGUAAAUCCACAGCCACUCUCUACUCCGAGCUGGCAGAUUGAGACCAAGUAUUCAACGAAAGUGCUCACUGGAAAUUGGAUGGAAGAGAGGAGAAAGUUCACCAGAGACACUGACAAGACACCCCAAUCCAUUUACAGAAAAGAAUACAUCCCCUUCCCAGACCACAGACCAGACCAGAUCUCCAGGUGGUAUGGGAAGAGGAAAGUUGAGGGGCUACCUUACAAACACCUGAUCACCCACCACCAGGAGCCCCCACAUCGCUACCUGAUCAGCACCUAUGACGACCAUUACAACCGGCAUGGUUACAACCCGGGGCUGCCUCCACUCCGCACUUGGAAUGGACAGAAGUUGCUGUGGCUGCCAGAGAAGUCUGACUUUCCCCUUCUUGCUCCCCCUACAAACUAUGGACUCUAUGAGCAGCUCAAGCAGAGACAGCUCACACCCAAGGCUGGCCUGAAGCAGAGCACUUAUACUUCAUCCUACCCCAGACCACCGUUGUGCGCUAUGUCCUGGAGGGAGCAUGCGGUCCCGGUCCCUCCCCAUCGCCUGCAUCCUCUCCCACACUUCUGAGAGCUGCCACCCCAGGAGCAGCUCAGAUAGAAUCAGCUGGAGACCACAGCAUCACUGGACUUGCCAGACAACAAGUGGCGCAGAUAAACUCAGAGUACGAGAUCUGGCCCGUCAAAGGUGCUCUCAGAAUCAUCAUCUGCAUUUGGCGGUACCUGUCCCCCCUCAAAACCCACAGGUUCCUUUCUUUUCCAUCCAACAAUUAAAGAUCUUUGACACUAUUGCAGGGCUAUGUACGUGCACAAGACAGAUUCAGACUGUCAGAGAAAACAGGAAGGGCCCUUAAGUUCUACCCUGUUGUUUCACAAGAGGGGAAACUGAGGCCCGGAGAGGUAAUGUGACUUGCUGAAGAGUCUACUCCCAUGGAGGAAAUGAAUCUGAUGAUGAAACCCAUCAUGAAAACUCCACAGAAUGACUGAAUGUGGUUCCCAGGAGGGCAGUGCUGCAGAGCUGGCAAUGGGGAAGGACCCCAGCUUGUCUGUCAUUGCCAAGGCAGAGGAAGGCGUGCUCUGGCCCCACGGGGCUCAGAAGAAGGGGAAAACACAUGGCAUUUCCUUUGUCUCUGAGCUCGCAAAUCUUUGUGUUUUUUUUUUUGUUUUUUUUUUUGAGACGGAGUGUCGCUCUCUUGCCCAGGCUGGAGUGCCGUGGCACGAUCUCAGCUCACUGCAACCUCUGCCUCCAGGGUUCAAGCGAUUCUUUUGCCUCAGCCUCCUGAGUAGCUGGGACUACAGGUGCGCACCACUACGCCUGGCUAAUUUUUGUAUUUUUAGUAGAGACAGGGUUUCACAAUGUUGGCCAGGCUGGUCUCGAACUCCUGACCUCGUGAUCCGCCUGCCUCGGCCUCCCAAAGUGCUGGGAUUAGCAGGCGUGAGCCACCGCACCUGGCUGAGCUCUCAAAUCUUUAUGAGCCUGGGCAGAGGGGAGAACCUCUGGUGAGUGAUUUGGGAGAGAGGGUGGAUCUCCUAGCAGAAGAACUCAGGCAUGGUCCUCGCCCAGGACAGGGGUCCACAAGUGUGCAUGCUCAGUGCUCGCACAGAGCUGCCUCUUUGAAGAAAUUCCAGCAGACACCUUUGGCCCUUUGCAUGCUUGGCUCAUGGGCACAGGUGUGUUUUGUCAGUGAUUUUGUACUGCACACCAAUAAUAUGACUCCCAGUAUGGGAGCCUGAGUCUCUGCCAUUGUUUUCACAGGAUACCUGCUGGCCUCAGGCCACCUACCUUAGGGUCACUUUGGCACCUACUAAGUUCCUUCCUUAGUCAUCCAAGUGUCCAUGUAAGGACGCUGUCUUCCAUCCCAACUGAAAGUCAGAGCCUGACACAGGCUAAGUCCUCUAUGUUUGUUGGAUGAGUGAAUGACAGGAGUUGAACAAAUGAGUUGAAUGAAUGAAUGACAGGAGGAGGAGCCAGGGGGUGCAGAAAGGUUGCACCUACCUUAGGGUCACUUUGGCACCUACUAAGUUCCUUCCUUAGUCAUCCAAGUGUCCAUGUAAGGACGCUGUCUUCCAUCCCAACUGAAAGUCAGAGCCUGACACAGGCUAAGUCCUCUAUGUUUGUUGGAUGAGUGGAUGACAGGAGUUGAACAAAUGAGUUGAAUGAAUGAAUGACAGGAGGAGGAGCCAGGGGGUGCAGAAAGGUUGCUGCAGGAGACAGCUGUGGGAUGGAGUGGAGCUGGCUGUCCUCACACCUCCAACAUCCAGCCUUUCUAUUGAGCAUCCAUUGAGCCAUGUCUGGGCCAGGCCCUGACCUCACAGAGCCUCAGUCCAGCAGUCAGGGAGGAGCAUGAGGUAAAUGGCUGCAGGACAGAGAGGUGCUGCAGCUGGAGGCCCUGGGGGACAGCGAUGGAUUGCGAGGAGUGAGGGAGACCCAGGAUAUGCUAAGCAGGGGCGUCUAAUCUUUUGGCUUCCCUGGGCUACAUUGGAAGAAGAAUUGUCUUGGGCCACACAUAAAAAAAUGAACAGGGGCUGGGCGCAGUGGCUCAUGCCUGUAAUUCCAGCACUUUGGGAGGCCUAUAUGGGCGGAUCACCUGAGGUCAGGAGUUUGUGACUAGCCUGUCUAGCACAGUGAAACACUGUCUCUAUUAAAAAUACAAAAAUGAGCUGGCAUAGUGGUUCAUGCCUGGAAUCCCAGCUACUCCAGAGGCUGAGGCAGCAGAAUCGCUUGAACCCAGGAGGCGGAGGUUUCAGUGAGACCAGAUGGUACCACUGCACUCCAGCCUUGGUGACAGAGUGAGACUCCAUCCCAAAAACAACAACAACAACAACAAACUUACACUAACGGUAGCUGAUGAGCUAAAAAAAAAAUCGCGUAAAAAAACCCCAUAAUGUUUUAAGUAAGUUUACAAAUUUAUGUUGGGCCACAUUCAGCCUGCAGGCGGAGGGUUGGACAAGCUUGUGCGAAAGUAAAGGAUGUCAUGAGAGCAACGGGCAGGGGUUGACGGAUGAUGAAUGAAGACCUGGCCUGCCUAGGUAGGGCCAGGGAGAAUCAGGUAGGUCAAGGCCAGAAAGCUGAGGGAGAUUACCCAGCUGAAGGGACAGGUUGGGAGGGAAGAGAGGGUGGCUUGGGCCAUGGGGGCAACACGUUUGAAGUCUCUGACUUGGGAAGAAGCUGAGCAAAUUCCUUAAAAGUCCAGAAAGACCAUGCAUUGGUCUCCUAUUGCUGCUGGAACAAAAUACCACAAACUCAGUGCCCUAAAGCAACACAUGUUUAUUUGACAGUUCUUAUUAUAAAUGUGAAUAAAUGCACAUUUAUUCAGAA